GCCUGCGCAUUAUGCUGGUCUCCAUGGCGGGGCCUCGGAGCCAAGACGAGGUUGAGUAGACUCGUUUUGAAUUUUCUCCCCUCUGCUCCGGCGGACUUCCCAUGUCGCCUUGUGGGGCUAUCGGCGGCGGCAGGACUGGGGGAGUCAGAGGUCUGGCAGCGCUGUCUGCGCAGACCUACCGGACGCUACCUCCCAACCCCCCGUCUUCCUCCUGCCUCCUCCUCCUCCCGUCACCUCCUGACCCGCCGGAGCUCCGAGCAACUGCCGGCCUCCGCCCCCAGCCGCAGCCGGUCACUGGCGGCGCCUUCCGCGCCAAGCUUGGGGGCCUUUUCGGGGUCCCACAUGGCACGGCUUCCGACCCCCGGCCCGGGACGGGGCUCGCAGGCCCCAGAGGGGCAGGCUGGAGAAGGAGGAGGUUAGGUGUCUUCAGGAGGGUUGCUGAGCCCAAGGACGCGCCAUCGCCGCGGAGAAGGAGCCGGACCCCUUGGGCGGAGCGCCCAAUGUGUGGUCCCUCACGCCGUCCCGCACCUUGCUUUUUAGGGUUCUUUUUCCGCUUUCUGAGCCCUUUUAUACCUUACGUUUAGAAGGGGAAAAUCAUCCUCCCACACCUUCUCCCCGACUUUUUGCCUUUUUUGUCUUGAAGUUACCCAAAGGCCUGUGUAUUGUUCUCAAUGGUCCCAAGAAUUACUCUAAUAUAGUUGUUUUUCUGAGGGAGGAUGGAUGGAGAUAACUAUCCUGAUCCCAAUGUCACUUUUUAAGGCAUUCGCUUCAAGAGACAAGCAGUUUAGAAUCAGGCAGAACUGGAUUGCAAAAUUUAUGGGCAGACCGAGAAAAUGCUGCUGUGAAGACCCAAUUAAAGCUUUCACAUAAAUGAAGCUACAGCUAUCAUGAUUUAGUGCCCCCAAAAGGAAGAACUUCAGUGGACAAGAAAGGACAUUUCUGGGGGUAGUAGAAUGCUUGAGGCCUGGAAUUUAAACCUGAGCCACUAUCUGAAGGUUUAAUAUAUCUUUGCCAAGUCCAAGGGUACAAAGAUUUUCUCCUGUGUUUUCUUCUAGAAGUUUUAUCAUUUGAUAGUCUGUGAUCCAUUUCAAGUUGAUUUGCUAUCUGGUGUGAGCUAUUAAAUAAUAGAAGAAAAUGGAAUUGAAUAUGAUGUCAGCAUGGAACAAUCUAAUGAUUCAUUAAGAGUCAACCAUAAUGACGGUGAAGAGUCAAAAACCAGUGCUCAAGUAUUUGAGCAUCUAAUCUGUAUGGACUCCAGGGAUUCUUCCUUUGGACAAAAUGAUUCUCCUACAGUUUUGCCCAUCACUACUCGUGAAGCAAAUAAUUCACUCAUAUCACAGAAUAUACCAGGGCCCCUGACUCAGACACAGACUCUUUCUGCAGAGCAAUUCCAUCUAGUGGACCAAAAUGGGCAGGCUAUUCAAUAUGAACUUCAGUCAUUGGGGGAAUCCAAUGCACAAAUGAUGAUCGUUGCCAGCCCAACAGAAAAUGGACAGGUACUUCGUGUAAUUCCACCUACCCAGACAGGAAUGGCACAAGUGAUUAUACCUCAGGGGCAACUUGUGGAUGUGAAUAGUCCUCGGGAUGUCCCUGAAGAGAAACCCAGUAACAGAAACUUACCAACUGUAAGAGUGGAUACUCUAGCAGACAAUACCAGCAAUUACAUUCUUCAUCCUCAAACAUCCUUCCCAUUGCCCAAAAAGUCAGUGACCGGAAUGCUGGAAGAACCCCUUCUGGGGCCUCUUCAGCCACUUUCUUCUAAUACACCUAUAUGGGCCUGCCGUCUUAGGAGCUGUGAGAAAAUUGGAGAUUCAUACCGUGGCUACUGUGUAAGUGAGACUGAAUUAGAAAGUGUCCUAACAUUUCACAAGCAGCAAACACAGAGUGUUUGGGGGACCCGUCAGUCUCCAAGCCCAGCCAAGCCUGCUACACGCUUGAUGUGGAAAUCCCAGUAUGUUCCAUAUGAUGGAAUCCCAUUUGUUAAUGCAGGGAGUAGAGCUGUGGUAAUGGAGUGUCAGUAUGGGCCAAGAAGAAAAGGUUUCCAGUUAAAAAAAGUCAGUGAGCAGGAAAGCAGGUCUUGUCAGCUCUACAAAGCCACUUGUCCAGCUCGGAUUUACAUUAAAAAGGUACAGAAGUUUCCUGAAUAUAGAGUUCCUACAGACCCCAAAAUUGACAAGAAAAUUAUCAGAAUGGAGCAGGAGAAAGCUUUUAACAUGCUAAAGAAGAACUUGGUAGAUGCUGGUGGUGUUCUUAGGUGGUAUGUACAGUUACCUACACAGCAAGCUCAUCAGUAUCAUGAAUUAGAGACUCCCUGCCUCACUUUGUCACCUUCUCCUUUUCCUGUGUCUUCUCUUGAAGAAGAGGAAACUGCAGUUAGAGAUGAGAAUUGUGCAUUACCCUCACGUUUACAUCCUCAAGUAGCACAUAAGAUUCAAGAAUUAGUAUCACAGGGAAUAGAACAAGUGUAUGCAGUAAGGAAACAGCUAAGAAAAUUUGUGGAAAGGGAACUGUUCAAACCCGAUGAGGUACCUGAAAGACAUAAUUUAUCUUUUUUUCCAACUGUAAAUGAUAUAAAAAAUCACAUCCAUGAGGUACAGAAAUCCUUGAGAAAUGGAGAUACGGUAUAUAACUCAGAGAUUAUUCCAGCAACGCUUCAAUGGACUACAGACAGUGGGAAUAUUCUCAAAGAGACCAUGACAGUUACAUUUGCAGAAGGAAAUUCACCAGGAGAAUCAAUUACCACCAAAGUGGAAACAAAUCAGACCAGGGGUUCUUUGUCUCCUGAGCCAACCCACUUGCUCUCCUCACUCUCCUCAUUUCAGCCCAAAAUAUUUACACAACUACAGGGUUUGCAGUUACAACCAAGGUACACCUCUCCUGAUGAAUCACCAGCUGUGGUAUCAGUAAAUAACCAGCCGUCCUCUAGUCCUUCAGGACUUCUGGAUACAAUAGGAAGUGCUGUAAUGAAUAAUAAUUCUCUACUGCUUGGUCAAAGUCAUAGCCUUCAAAGAGAUACAUGCUUAACCCAAAACAAUAGUACUGCCUCCACCAUGGGUAACCUUCCAGAACCAGAUCAAAAUCUAGUUGCAAUGGACGAGCUGGUAGAAGUUGGAGAUGUUGAGGAUACAGGGAAUCUGGAAGGAACUGUUCAUCGGAUUCUGUUGGGAGAUGUGCAGACUAUUCCAAUACAGAUUAUAGACAACCACUCAGCUCUUAUUGAAGAAAAUCCAGAAAGUACCAUUUCUGUGAGCCAAGUUAAACAAGAACCCAAAGAACCAGCAUUGUCUAUGGAAGCAAAAAAAACUGUGGACUAUAAGAAAUUAUCUGCUACAUAAAUUAUUGAAGCUUUUCAGAAUUUACAACUCUGGUGACUUCUGAUGUCUUAGAAAGGAAGGUGAAUAUAGUCAAAGCGUGGCAUUGAGAUAAUUGGACUGAAGACCAGUUUGAUGAGAAGCUUUUAUUUAAAACUGAUAUAUUUGUUGCCAGUUCCAUAUUUUUACCUUCCUUAAGAGAUGUUUUACUCUUCUUAUUUUGUAUAAUUUUUAUGCUCUUUGAUUAUCUAAUAAGGCCAGUAUUUCAAAAGCUGUUCUGAAUUUAUCCACAGUAAUAUAGUCUGAACACAAAUAGUUUACUUAACUUAUCCUUGGAAAUAUUCAAUUUUGGUUAUUACAAAACAGAAAAGAACAACAGCAACAAAAACAUUGUGUGAAUGUAUGUUUGUAUGUGUGUAUGUAUAUCAUGAAUUUUUUUUUUAAGUUCUGAAAAAGAACUUGUUCUCUCCUUAAAGUUGUGAAGAAAUUGUUAAUUGCCAGACAGGUAAGAAAAUGUUUAUAAUCUAUCUCAUUAAGAAAGAUGAAGUAUUAGAUUUUACAUCAUAACACAAAGUCCAGCAGCUACAUCUGUGGAAACUGUGCAGUUGCAUUUUAGCCUCUUCCCUUCCAAUUUUUGUACUUUUAACUACAAACCAGUAGUAUACUAAUGGUUAUCUAAUAGAAAUUUAAAGUGUCUUGGUAAGUACUGAGAAUUUUUACUUGAAUUAAUCAGAUAAGCAACAGAAAUCAACAUAUGUAGCAUGGAUUUGUGCUAUAUUGGAAGUAAAACACUAUAGGCAGAAAGAUGUAGAAAUUAAGAGAAUUGAAAAAGAAUAAUAGAAUUCCUUGGUGUUUACAGAUAAUUUGGAAAACUUUUUGAUGACAGCAGAGGAUUUUUUCCCCCUUAUUUUGUAAUGAAGAUCCAGCACUGGUUAAAAAAUAAUUUGAUUUGUAGUUACAUUUUUCUAUGCCAGAGCUCUUACUGAAUUGAUGAUAUUAGGAUUUCUAGUAUUUUAAGGUAAGUAUUUAUAGUUUAAAAUUUAGUUUAUAUUUAAAACUUUAAAACAUCUGAUCUGGGAUUUUUUUGUUAAGUAAGUAUAUUAACUUCAAAUACCAAAUUACUACUAAGCAGUAUAUUGAUUAUAAGCAUCUGUUGUCUAAAGAUUGGUACUAGGCUGGACAUGGUGGCUCACACCUGUAAUCACAAUACUUUGGGAGGCUGAGGUGGGUAGAUAACCUGAGGUCAGGAGUUCGAGACCAGCCUGGCCAACGUGGUGAAACCCUGUUUCUACUAAAAAUACAAAAAUUAGCUGGGUGUGGUGGUGGGCACCUGUAAUCCCAGCUACUUGGGAGGCUAAGGCAGGAGAAUCGCUUGAACACCGGAGGCGGAGGUUGCAAUGAGCCGAGAUCGCGCCAUUGCACUCCAGCCUGGGUGACAAGAGAAAAACUCCAUCUCAAAAAAAAAAAAAAGAUUGGUAAACUAGAAAUAUCAACUAUAAUUGUCAGGAAAUUAACCUAAAGGCUUUUGUUUCUCCAGAGACCAUUUGUGGGUAUAUUUUAUAUUUUAAAAAUAAAGAUUUUAAAUGGAUAUCAAUGUUUAAUAUUCAAAACAUGCACAAUAUAAUAUCAAAUUUAACCUUAAUACUUUACAUGAAUAUGAGUCACUUUUGGCUUUUCUAAGUCCAGCCUCCCAUUCUUAAUUGACUUGGUUUCAGGUACAUGACAUGUAUCUAAAUAUAAAGUACUGUUAUAGUAGAGGUAGGUGGAAUUCUAAUAUUCCCUGCUCUUUAGAUUUAUAUUUUAUUUAAUAUAAAGUUUAUUAUUUAUACCCUUUUUAAUGCAAAGCUAAUAUUUAGUUAUAUGUAUGAUUUUUAAUAAAAAUUACUUUACUUUUUCCUAUGAAUUUAAAACAUUUGAUGUUGGCAUUUUAUACAGGCAGGUUGCCAAAUUUAAUUAUGUUACACUAAGUUAAACACAGCACUUAAUUACCUCAAAUCCAGAUUUCUCUUAAUCUGUGUGUACAUAAAAGGAAUAAGUCCAAAUUAAUUUAUAGUUUAGUGUUGCACUAUAGGUAAUAUUCUUUUGUUAUUUCUAGUUUUUAUGGAAUCCUUUUCUUUCAAGAUUCUAAAUAAUAAAUCGUUACGUCUCAAUAGUGGUAAUAGUGGUAAUGGUUUAUUAUUAGCUGUUUCACCAAUUGAACUACAUUCUUUUGGAGACAUUCCUUUCUUUUUUGAUGUUGAUUUGCAAAGGAGAAAUGCUUGUUAAUAUACAAACUCUAGUCAGUUACCUGUGAGGAUGAGAUGUGUCAGAGGACUCAGACUUUGGUAUAGUUAGAAAAAUAAUAUUUUUCUCACUUGAUUCUGUGUGAAUGUCUCUUCUGAUACUGUUUUUUAAUCAGAAAGUUACAGAGCAACUUUCCCACAAACAAACCAAUAAAACAAAACCCCACAAAAACCAAGAGCAUGAAGAAAAGUUUAAAUCCCUAAUUAUAUACUCUUUUGGUUUUUAGGUAGAAACUGGAGCUAUCAAUAUUUUCAUGUAAGUAUUUCAAGGAGUAGCUCUUUAAAAAUGGUUUCUAAAUUAGAUUUUAAAAAUUCAUUGUCAUCUAAAUGCAUGUUUAGUCACAAUGUAUCAGUAUUGUGUUUAAAGGUGCUCAGCAUCACUUUUUGAAAACUAUGUUUACAUAUUUAAAAUGUUUAAUUAUUUUGAAAUGUAUAGGGUAUUAAAUACAAGCUUCUAAAAUUUUCAGUAUCUAUAUUGGCUUUCUCUAACAGCUCUACAGCAAAGUUUGACAUGUUUUUUGUGUGUGUCAUGUAUUGUAAGUUGUAAUAUCUGUAGGAGUGAGUUGGACAUUCUAAAUUAGCAGUAAAAAAUUCACAAUUACAGCUCAGCUUGUUUAUUCAUUAUAGUUUCCACAUUUCCAACUUCCAAGUGAACUUUAUAUAUACUACAGUGAAUUAUAGAUAAAUACAGCCAUGGUGGACCUUUCCCUCAAUAGUGAUUUUUUGUACAAACAGUUAGUAUAAUUAAAAGGAAAAGCUUUUAUAUUUUAUGCAAGGUAAAUGUUUCCUAAAUGUCACAAAAGUGAUAGAAAACAUAGCUUUUGGGAUCUGGUCCUGCAUUAGAGUUUCUAAUUCUGAGACCCACCAGCUUGUGUUUCAUCUUCUUUAUAUCCUGUCAGAAUACAUACUUAAUCAUGUGGGUAUGAGAAAGAUGUUGUUUAACUUGUACCAGGUUUAAAAAAAGAGGUUUAAAAAAUGUCUGUGCGUAUAUAUAUAUAUAUAUAUAUAUAUAUAUAUAUAUAUAUAGCAACUUGAUGUAUAGUGUCCUUGUUACCAUGUAUUUUUUUCAUUAAAAAUCCUGCUUUUUUUUUAUACUUGUUAGUUUUCUUUUUAUAUUUUUCUUAGAGAUAGUGGCAAUUUUGUUCAUCUUGAAGAUGCUGAAUAAACACUUGAAUACCCGAGAAUUUUGGCCAGAGAUUUAUGUCCAAUUUGGAACCUGAAAGUUUUAAGCAUAACUACAAGUAACUCCUGUUAGCAUUACAUUUUGGGGAGACAUAUAUGCAUUUAAUACCCUGCAACUCAGCCAAGCAUCAACAUUUUAAAACAAUGUGUGUAAUAAGUAAUUCUCCACGCCCACCCACCCCCAGCCCCCCGAUGUUUUGGCACCAUGACAUUUUCAAGUAUAGCUUUAUAUUUUAGGAGUAAUGACAAAGUAUGUGAUCAAAAGAGAAGGGAUUAUUAAUUUUUUCCCUCUUUGCUUUUUUUUAAACUUUAUUCCACUCUGUACCUAUUUUUGAGGACCUUGAAAAUCUUAAUCUCUCCAGAAGGGAUACUGCAUUGGUUCUUCUCCAUCAGCUGGCUUAGACAUCAAACAUCUUAAAUGAUACACUGUUUUAAUAUCUAAAAAUCUGUCAUUCUACUUAAUUAACUUAGUCAUAAGGACAAAGCCUUAGUAUAUUUUUGCCACAUACAUGUUAUGUAUAAAUUUUACUGUUGAAUAAUACAAGUAUUCAUUGCUGACUGAAUUCUUAAAACUUUGGGAAUAGAAAAAACACAUUUAUUAAUGGAUGCUAAAGUGAUUCCUGAGAAAAAUAAUGUGUAUGGUUAAUAUGGAAAACCUUUGGUAAUGUGAUUUGGGUAUAAGAAUACUAAAACCAGAGUACAGGGUGUGAAUCAUGUACCAGGAGGGAUUUUAUUUUUAAAUAUCUUUAUUGAGGUAUAAUUGAAAUACAAUAAACUGUACAUAUUUAAAGUACCCAAUAUGAUAAGUUUUGUCAUAUGCAUACAGCCAUGAAAUCAUCAGCAUAAGCAAGGUAAUGAACAUAUUCAUCACUCUCAAAGUUUCAUAGUACCUCUUUGUGAUCCCUUCUUACUUAAUCCUCCUUGCCACCCCACCAUCACCAGACCACUGAUCUGCUUUCUUUAUGAUCAGUUUGCUACAAAUGAAAUCACAUAAUAUGAACCUUUUUUGGUCUAGCUUUUGUCACUUAGCAUAGUAAUUUUGUGAUUUGUCUAUAUUGUUGCAUUUAUGAAUAAAUCAUUUAUCUGCUGCUGAGUAGAACUGCAUUUUAUGAAUAUAUCAAUUUGUUUAUUCUUUUGAUGAUGGACAUUAAUAGUUCUAGGCUAUUAUGAAUAAAGUUUCCAUGAACAUCUAUGUACAA